AGAAUUAUGGCGACCUCCGCGACGUCGCCGCACGCGCCUGGUUUUCCAGCUGAGGGUAGAUGCGGUUACUAUGUGGAAAAGAAGAAACGGUUCUGCAGGAUGGUGGUGGCCGCAGGGAAAAGAUUUUGUGGUGAACACGCUGGAGCCGCGGAGGAAGAAGAUGCUCGGAAAAGAAUCCUGUGUCCUUUAGAUCCAAAACACACAGUAUAUGAAGAUCAACUAGCAAAGCAUUUGAAAAAAUGUAACUCAAGAGAGAAACCAAAACCUGAUUUCUAUAUUCAAGAUAUUAAUGCAGGCUUAAGAGAUGAAACAGAAAUACCUGAACAAUUAGUUCCAAUUUCUUCUCUAUCUGAAGAGCAGUUGGAAAAGUUAAUUAAGAAAUUGAGAAAAGCAAGUGAAGGCUUGAAUUCUACACUUAAAGAUCAUAUUAUGUCCCAUCCAGCAUUACACGAUGCACUUAAUGACCCUAAAAAUGGCGAUUCUGCAACCAAGCACCUGAAACAGCAGGCUUCUAUUUUAGGUAACAUUGAAAAUUUAAAGUUACUUGGUCCAAGAAGAUGCUUUGUUGAGUUUGGAGCGGGAAAGGGAAAAUUAUCUCAUUGGGUUGAUAUUGCCUUAAAAGAUGCUGAAAAAGUUCACUUCAUCCUAGUGGAAAAGGUGACCACAAGAUUCAAGGUGGAUGGAAAACACAGAAAGAAAAAUUCAGUGUUUGAAAGACUUCAAAUUGAUAUUCAACACUUGUGUUUGAACAAGAUUCCUGUGCUAAGAGAAGAAAAACUACCUGUGGUAGGAAUUGGAAAGCAUCUGUGUGGUAUGGCAACAGACGGAGUCUCGCUCUGUCGCCCAGACUGGAGUGCAGUGGCGCAAUCUCGGCUCACUGCAACCUCCGCCUCCCGGCUUCAAGCGAUUCUCCUGCCUCAGCCUCCCGAAUUGCUGGGACUACAGACUCGUGCCACCACGCCCGGCUAAUUUUUGUAUUUUUAGUAGAGACGGGAUUUCACCGUGUUAGCCAGGAAGGUCUCCAUCUCCUGACCUCGUGAUCUGCCCACCUCAGCCGGCGUGAGCUACUGCGCCUGGCCUGAAAUAACUUAAUUCUUUUAAUAAUUUAUCUGGUUAUUCACAUUUCUGAAAAUCACUUACUUAAGUCAAAUAUGAAUAAAACAAUGACUAAAUGUAUUUUGUCAGAAAAUAAUAGUUUAUGAAAUAAUAGAUUAGCUAUCACUUUCUGCAAAUAAUGGGUUUCUAAUGUUUGUUGACUUAAAUUCAUAUAUUGAAUUAAAUUUACUAGUGAAAUAUCAGAUCAUUUAAUAGUCAUUUGUGAUAUCUUAGGGUAAUAAAAUUUUAAAAUAUGUAUAUGUUUUUGAUUGAACAGACACAACAUGACAAUCUAAUGAUUAAGAAGAUAUGGGUCCUACAUUUUGGGUCUUUCCAGUAUUGUCAACAGUGUAGGAGUUUUCGAUGGGAAAUAGCCAUAGUCAUCAAAAAUCCAUUUAUUUAGUUUUAAAAUAUACUAAAAUAUUUUCAUUGUAAUGUGGAGUACAUCUGCCUCUUAAGUUUGUGUAUAUUAAUAAUUGUAUCCUCAGUGCUUUGCACAUGAAAGGCAUUCAGUAAAUGUUUGUUAAAUAAAUGAAUAAAUACAGUAAGGCUACUCAGUGAGGCCUGCUUUCCAGAUUCUGUUCUGACGCCCUCUUUUCAACUCUUCAGUUCAUCACUAUUUGCUAUGAGCCUCUUCAAGACAAGCAUCUUGACCUAGCAUCAACCUAAACAGAUUUGUCUGCCCUUCCUCCCUCCCUUCCUUCCUUCCUUCAUUUUUCCUUUCUUAAACUAGAAUGUAAGUGUAGGUGAAUAAAGUUUUCCCAUACAAGUCAUUUCCUCAGCUAAGGUAGGAAAAGUGAGAGACAAUUCAGGUAGUUGGGUAAAAGUUCUUCAAAUUGUAGAUCUUAAGCUUCAGAUAGCUUUAUUGGGAAGUAGGCUUUAUGCAGAAUAAAUCAUUAAAGAAAUUGAGAAGAUAGAAGAGCAAAUUUGAAUGAAGUUGAUAAUUCAUGAUAGUAUUAUUACAAAUAUAAAGCUGAGUAGGUUUUUGCUGUUUUUAUUGUUGAGUUUUUAAAAACAGUACUGCUUAAUAAAUGUAAAAAGUAUUUAUUUUUAAAGAUGAUGUGGUUUGGGGGGGCCACAUAAUUGUGUUUGCAGAUCUUGCAUUACGAUGUUUGGUUGAAACCUAUGCUGCCAGUUUUGAGGAAAGGAAUGAAGAACCUUUAGCCAAACGCAUAAAGAAUGAUAAAACAGAAAAAGAAAUUUACACUUUGGCCAAGGAAGGAAAUGAAAAAAAUGUCCCAGAGAAGUGGAACCCUGUGGCUGGCAUUGUUAUUGCACUCUGUUGUCACCACAGGUGUGAUUGGAGACAUUAUGUGGGCAAAGAAUAUUUCAGGGCUCUAGGCCUUGGAGCAGUGGAAUUCCAUUAUUUCCAGCGAAUGAGUAGUUGGGCAACUUGUGGGAUGCGGAAAACAUCUUUGGAAACCUCAAAUAGUACCACAAAGAGGCAAGAUAAUCAGAAUGAUGAUAGUGAAGAGCAUGAUGAUGGAGGAUACAGAAUCACAGAUGAUGGCGCUGAUUGUUUGCCUGGGUAAGAGACUACUUUUGUAAUGCAUGAUACUAAAGGAGAAAUAUUAUAUUGUACUGUACUUUAGAUGACUAUUAUCAACAAUUCAUGAAAAUGUAUUUUAUAAUCUAAUUUUAGAAUAAGCUAAAAUAUACACAUCUUUUAUUGUGGUCAUAAAUAUAAUGUGUCUUGGAAGCAUGGGACAAAGUACUUAGUACAUUAUGGGUUAGUUAACAGUCUCUCAAUAAAUAGUGACAAAAAUAAUUUUUUAUAAACUUUUGCAAAAUUUUAACAAUGUUUUGUGUGUGUUUAUUCAAUUUAGGCUUCUUAGUGUUGAAGAAAAGAAGAAAAUAGGGCAUCUUUGUAAAUUGCUGAUUGACCAAGGUCGAAUCCAGUAUUUGCAGCAGAAGGGAUUCAGUCCUGCUUUGCAGUACUAUACAGACCCUCUGGUGUCUUUGGAAAAUGUUUUGUUAACUGCUUUACCAAAUCAUUCUUCAUCACCAGAAACAACUGCUUAAUGGAAAAGAAAUUUGAGCAUCAUCUGUCUUCCACCAAAAAAAAUUUUUUAAUUAUAUUUUUAUAUCAAAAAAAUAUAUACUUUAAAUAGCAAAUAAUAUGAACUUUAAAAAAUGCUGUGGCCUCAUUAAACUUUGGUAAUAGCUUUUCUUUUUACUUCAGAAAUCCAAACAUUAGAGAAUUCACCAAAGUAAUCCUCUUUAGAAGGGCAUCUUGAAUUAUAUUAUCCAUCCGUAUUUAUGGAGAUUGGUAAAGUAGUUGAACCGUUGACUUGGUGAUCUGAAACAUACAUAACAUGUCAACACAUAAUUAGCGUAUUUCUGUUUGUAUUAAUUUUGGAAAUUUAUCUUCCUUUGAUUUUAUUUAAUAUUUUUUAUUUCUUAAGUUCAAGAGGUAGUGAUUGAUUGUAACAAGGGCCAAUCUGAGAAUUUGACUUAUAUGUGGACAUUUUUCCCUACAGAUCUGGAAAGCACAAUUGUGAUUUUCUCAAAUGCAGACAAUUCAGAGAUAUUCACAAUUAAUAAACACAAUUAAUUAAUGAAGUCACCUUCAAAUUUCCAGAGCCAUACAUGUAUAUAUUGUCAGAAUCUGUCCAUGACAAACACAAAACUGAAGAGCUGUUUUCAAAGAAAAAAGAUUAUUUCACUUAAUUAUUUUGUUGGAUAAUUGUCUAGUUAGAACUUCCAAAAAGAUACUUACAAACAUAAUUCACAAAUUUGAAAUAAUUUCUGAAGUUGAUUAGCUAUCUCAUAUCUUUUAUCAGGUCAUUUUUUAUAUAUGUAGGCACAAACAAUAAGUAUGUUCUCUUCUGUUUGGGAAAAUAAUUUGGAAUAAAAUAGAAAUUAGAUAAUGAAACCAAAAACCUUCUCAAAUUUAGGCCUUAUUUAACUCAUGACUGGUUUCUAUGCACAAGAAAAUACUAAACCAAAUAUAUGGUAGGACUGUUAUUCUCUUCUGCAUCUUAUCCCUAUUUUGUUUCUGCCUUUAUUUGUAAAAAUUGUCUUAAUUGAUGGUACAUUUGCCAAGACAAAGGUUCAGAAUUACUAAUUUUAGAUAUUAUGAUAUUCUGAAAUAACUAUUUUUAUCCUGUAGUUCUAUGAUUAUAUGAUUUGUAAAUAAGAAGCCUAACCAAUUUAAAAUUCCUGACUUUAGUCUCAUAUAUCUUGUCAGACUGUCUCGGUUCAAAUUCCAAACCUACCAUCUUCAGUUGUGCGACCUUGGGCAUGCUACCUAAUCUCUUUGUGCCUCAAUUUCCUCCUUUUAAAAUGGGGAUGAUGAUGAUAACAAUAAUACCUACCUCACAAGGUUGUUGUGAGCAUCAAAUGAGAUAACACAAGUAAAAUGCAUAGAACAGUUCCAAGCACAGAGUAAUUCAAUAAAUAUUAACUAGUAAUAGUAGUGGUAGUAACUCGUGAAUCUUUUUAAUAACAUAAUAGGCUUUGAUUUUAUUAUCUCUUUAAGUUGUUAACUUUUUUCCCUUGUUAUAAGUUUUAUGUCAAGUAAGGUAGUUUGUUUAAGUUAGUUACCCAUGUCCCCAAUCAAGGGAACCUAAAUGAAGAUAUAUCAUUAAAUAAUUAACCUUUUUUUAUUGUGUCAAGCAAUACUAAUUUGUGUCAUAAAAUUUGUUUUGCAUCAUUCAACAAUUUAUGCCCAGAAAUAAACAAUAUUCUACAACAGG